AAGCAAGUGUCAGGGCUCACCAACCAUGCAAGGACAGGGCAGGAGAAGAGGAACCUGCAAAGUGGGUAAAGUCUUUCCUUCACAAUCAGGAGUAACACUUCAUGCCGGUGCUCCUAGGAGAAGAGUUGGUGGCAGCCAUUCACACUGUAGUAUAAAUGACUAAAGAGCAAAGUCUGAUGAAGGGCAAGGGGGAUUAUGAAGGCACUGUGCUUGUGAAAAGGAUGAUGGGGGGAAGGACAUCCAGGUCAUGGGGGGGAAAUUAUAAAAUUUGUGAGAAGAGAAAAGCCUUCAGACGGAUGUGACCUAUUGGAGCACACACCUGCUUUGCUUUCCCCUCUGGCUGAGCACAGACCUCCCCUGGCCUUGCAUUGGAUUCAUACACCUUCCUUCUCUAAAAUGACCACUUACUGUUGUAUCUCAGGGUCAACGCACAGGGUUGGAGCUCCUCUGUAAAGUUGUGUUAAAGGAAAUGAAAUCUUUCUGAUGAAACUGAACAGGUGAGGGUGCUGUAGGCAGGGCUGGGGAGACCUGUGAGCAGUACUUGAUAGAGUUGCUCCAAUCAAAUUCUCUCUGACUUCAACAAAACAACAGUAAAAGUAAUGUAUUCAGCGCUCACCAUGUGCUGGGUCCCGUGCUGCACAAUUUGUGCCUUAUCACACUCAGUCCUCUGAACAACUCUGUAAGGUAACUAUCUCUGUUUUACAAAGGCAAAACAGAGAAGUCCAGAGAGGUUACUUGUCCACCACGAAUGUCAGGGUUAGAUUCAAGCCCAGCCCUGUUGGGGUUUGAAAUUGCUAUCAGGUCAUUUAGUCUGAAGUCUCCUUGGGGCCAAAGCCAUGUCAGCUGAGGCUUGAAGGGGAAGCAGACAGAUGUGACUAGAACUGCAGCUCAUCAGCAACUGACUGCCAGUGCUCAGGGCACCUGAAGGAGCACAGCAAAAAGGACAGCCUUUUGCUCCAGGUUUCCACUUUUUGAGAGAUAUGAACACAUUAGUAAAAUGCCUGUGUCUGGGAACAGGCAGCCAGGGUGAGAAAAUAAUCAGAUCUACACAAAAUGGAUAAAGAAUGUGUGGAGGGACCUCCAAAGGGUGAGAAACCACUUCUGGCUGCUAAUGCAAUCUGGGUUCACAUACUCAAUUCUUAAAAAAUAAGUCCAUGAAGCAGAAACAUCAAAAAGCAUGGGAUUUGGAAUUUGAGACCUGACUUUGAAGCCCACACAGAACACAGACAAGUCAACCAUGCUAUUUGGGACAUAUUUUGUUCCAAAAUGGCAUCUUACCUUUAUGGAGUACUCUUUGCUGUUGGCCUCUGUGCUCCAAUCUACUGUGUGUCCCCGGCCAAUGCCCCCAGUGCAUACCCCCGCCCUUCCUCCACAAAGAGCACCCCUGCCUCACAGGUGUAUUCCCUCAACACCGACUUUGCCUUCCGCCUAUACCGCAGGCUGGUUUUGGAGACCCCGAGUCAGAACAUCUUCUUCUCCCCUGUGAGUGUCUCCACUUCCCUGGCCAUGCUCUCCCUUGGGGCCCACUCAGUCACCAAGACCCAGAUUCUCCAGGGCCUGGGCUUCAACCUCACACACACACCAGAGUCUGCCAUCCACCAGGGCUUCCAGCACCUGGUUCACUCACUGACUGUUCCCAGCAAAGACCUGACCUUGAAGAUGGGAAGUGCCCUCUUCGUCAAGAAGGAGCUGCAGCUGCAGGCAAAUUUCUUGGGCAAUGUCAAGAGGCUGUAUGAAGCAGAAGUCUUUUCUACAGAUUUCUCCAACCCCUCCAUUGCCCAGGCGAGGAUCAACAGCCAUGUGAAAAAGAAGACCCAAGGGAAGGUUGUAGACAUAAUCCAAGGCCUUGACCUUCUGACGGCCAUGGUUCUGGUGAACCACAUUUUCUUUAAAGCCAAGUGGGAGAAGCCCUUUCACCCUGAAUAUACAAGAAAGAACUUCCCAUUCCUGGUGGGCGAGCAGGUCACUGUGCAUGUCCCCAUGAUGCACCAGAAAGAGCAGUUCGCUUUUGGGGUGGAUACAGAGCUGAACUGCUUUGUGCUGCAGAUGGAUUACAAGGGAGAUGCCGUGGCCUUCUUUGUCCUCCCUAGCAAGGGCAAGAUGAGGCAACUGGAACAGGCCUUGUCAGCCAGAACACUGAGAAAGUGGAGCCACUCACUCCAGAAAAGGUGGAUAGAGGUGUUCAUCCCCAGAUUUUCCAUUUCUGCCUCCUACAAUCUGGAAACCAUCCUCCCGAAGAUGGGCAUCCAAAAUGUCUUUGACAAAAAUGCUGAUUUUUCUGGAAUUGCAAAGAGAGACUCCCUGCAGGUUUCUAAAGCAACCCACAAGGCUGUGCUGGAUGUCAGUGAAGAGGGCACUGAGGCCACAGCAGCUACCACCACCAAGUUCAUAGUCCGAUCGAAGGAUGGCCCCUCUUACUUCACUGUCUCCUUCAAUAGGACCUUCCUGAUGAUGAUUACAAAUAAAGCCACAGACGGUAUUCUCUUUCUAGGGAAAGUGGAAAAUCCCACUAAAUCCUAGGUGGGAAAUGGCCUGUUAACUGAUGGCACAUUGCUAAUGCACAAGAAAUAACAAACCACAUCCCUCUUUCUGUUCUGAGGGUGCAUUUGACCCCAGUGGAGCUGGAUUCGCUGGCAGGGAUGCCACUUCCAAGGCUCAAUCACCAAACCAUCAACAGGGACCCCAGUCACAAGCCAACACCCAUUAACCCCAGUCAGUGCCCUUUUCCACAAAUUCUCCCAGGUAACUAGCUUCAUGGGAUGUUGCUGGGUUACCAUAUUUCCAUUCCUUGGGGCUCCCAGGAAUGGAAAUACGCCAACCCAGGUUAGGCACCUCUAUUGCAGAAUUACAAUAACACAUUCAAUAAAACUAAAAUAUGAAUUCAUCUGUCAA